CUCUAUCUGCACAUCCUGGGGACGAACCGGGCAGCCGGAGAGCUGCGGCCGGCCCAGUCCCGCUCCGCCUUUGAAGGGUAAAACCCAAGGCGGGGCCUUGGUUCUGGCAGAAGGGACGCUAUGACCGCAGAAUUCCUCUCCCUGCUUUGCCUCGGGCUGUGUCUGGGCUACGAAGAUGAGAAAAAGAAUGAGAAACCGCCCAAGCCCUCCCUCCACGCCUGGCCCAGCUCGGUGGUUGAAGCCGAGAGCAAUGUGACCCUGAAGUGUCAGGCUCAUUCCCAGAAUGUGACAUUUGUGCUGCGCAAGGUGAACGACUCUGGGUACAAGCAGGAACAGAGCUCGGCAGAAAACGAAGCUGAAUUCCCCUUCACGGACCUGAAGCCUAAGGAUGCUGGGAGGUACUUUUGUGCCUACAAGACAACAGCCUCCCAUGAGUGGUCAGAAAGCAGUGAACACUUGCAGCUGGUGGUCACAGGAUCACUCCCAGAACCUUUGCUCUCAGUCAAUGUAGACCCUGGGAUGACUCCAGGUCUCAGGACACUUCGAUGUCUCACUCCAUACAAUGGAACCGAAUGUAUUGUAAUUGCUCUGUUGAAAAUGGGGAUCCCAGAACCAUUACAAGUCAGGCAAGUAAGAAAAAACCAGACUGAUUUCAUGCUCUGGAACGUGACAAGUAAUGACAGUGGAAACUACAGCUGUGUGUAUUACCUGAGCAACUCAUCACACUUGGCCUCCUUCCCCAGCAACAAGCUGGAGAUCUGGGUGACAGAUAAACACGAUGAACUUGAAGCUCCCUCAAUGAAAACAGAUGGGGAAACAGAAGCUUGGAGAAGAUUAAGGAAAUUCCCCAAAGCAAUAGGAAGUUCCAGCUCCGAGACACCAGAACCAUCUUUGUCGCCAUCUUCAGCUGCAUCUCCAUCCUUCUCCUCUUCCUCUCAGUCUUCAUCAUCUACAGAUGCAGCCAGCACAGUGAGCUCAGAGAACGCAAAGGGAGAGAGGGGGAGUGAAGGAUUUUCUCGAACCAGCCAUUCCAAACUUCCGGAGCAGGAGGCUGCCGAGGCAGAUUUAUCCAAUAUGGAAAGGGUAUCUCUCUCGACGGCAGACCCCCAAGGAGUGACCUAUGCUGAGCUAAGCACCAGCGCCCUGUCUGAGGCAGCUUCAGACACCACCCAGGAGCCCCCAGGAUCUCAUGAAUAUGCGGCACUGAAAGUGUAGCAAGAAGACAGCCCUGGCCACUAAAGGAGGGGGGAUCGUGCUGGCCAAGGUUAUCGGAAAUCUGGAGAUGCAGAUACUGUGUUUCCUUGCUCUUCGUCCAUAUCAAUAAAAUUAAGUUUCUCGUCUUAAAAAGAAA